GCAGCCGGAGUAUCCACCUCGAUGACCACGGGCUGAGCCCCGCGCCGCCACCAUGUCCGUGGCCUUCGCGUCUGCCCGGCCAAGAGGCAAAGGGGAGGUUACGCAGCAAACCAUCCAGAAGAGUCUUGCUCUUUCGCCCAGGCUGAGGUGCAGUAACGUGAUCACAGCUCGUGCAGCCUUGUCCUCCUGGGCUCAAGGGACAGGUGAGGUCUCUAUGUGCUGACAGAGGACAGUCUCCAAGAUGUUUGAGAGGAAAGGGAGCUGUGUGGAGCAGCGGGAGCGAAACGUUAUCAGGUGUGUGCAGAGUCGGGAGGGGAGUGCACAGGCUCCAUGCCAGACGCUUCCAGAAUCGGCAGAGCUGGCCUCUGGGGAAGAGGAGCCAGGGGUUCCUCCUGCAAAAUUAAAAAGGUUCCAAAAGUCUUUGUAAUUAGAAAGGACAACCAUGAGGACACUGGAGGUCUUCCUGCCCAGUGUGGGCUGAGCCAGCCCCGGCAGUGAGCCUCAGAGCCCCAGGCCUCCUCUGUCUGGCUUCCAGGGCCCCACACAGGUUGUCAUUGGGGAGAGACUGUUCUGCUGAGAGCCCCUCACCCAGGUUUUUGCCUGGUAGCCCCAGCCCUUCCCCUACUCUCUGUGGGCUCUGGGACCCCAGUUCUCCGUCCCUGGUUCUCAUCCUCACUCCCUCGCCUACCCAGUUAGGACCCCACGGUGGGGCUUCAGCAGCCCCAGACCCCAUCCUUGGUGCCUGGCUGUGCCCUGGGCCCUCCAAGCCAAGCCCCGUGUCCCCCGUCAGUCCCCGCUUGCCAAAUCCAGUUUCUCUGCUCACCCACAUGGUCCAUUGCCAUGGCCGUGGCUUCCGUGCCCCUUGGGUUUGUCUCCCUGUGGGUGCUGGGCUUGGCCCUGGGCAUCAGCCAGCCUGACCAACAGAGACACGUUGGGGCCACCCCUCAGAGCCUGAGACCACAGGGGUGACCACGCAGAGAGGGAGUGGGAGGCCCAGGUGUCCCAGCUGCCCCAGCCACGAGCCCAGCCAAGCCCAGCAGAAGAUCCUCCGAACCAGCCCAGAAUCAUGAGAACUAAGAAAUCAUGUUUCAACCACGCGGCUCCGGGAGGUUUGUUGCGCAUUGGGUAAUGGAUGCACCCAGCCGCGUUGGGAUCUUGGUCCAGCCAGUCUCUGCAGUGAGCACAGGCUUUGGUUGAGAAAGUCACCCCCACAAUGGGCACAGGACUCCUGUCCCCCAGCAGCCCCCGUUCCCCUCUUUUCCCGCUCCCCAUAGCUGGCCUCCCCCGUUCCCCUCUUUUCCCGCUCCCCAGAGCUGGCCUUCCCCGUUCCCCUCUUUUCCCGAUCCCCAGAGCUGGCCUCCCCCGUUCUCCUCUUUUCCCUCUCCCCAGAGCUGGCCUCCCCCGUUCCCCUCUUUUCCCGGUCCCCAGGGCUGGCCUCCCCCGUUCCCCUCUUUUCCCGCUCCCCAGAGCUGGCCUCCAUUCCUGGAGAUGCCCCGUGGCCUUCACACAUGCCUGUUUCCUCCAUCGGGCCGCCCUUCCCCCACCUUACCCAUGUGCUCCUGCCCAGCCUCCAGCCCAGCUGGACGUCAACCCCAGGAGUCUCCUGGGGCUCCGCUGCCUCAUGGCAUUGAGCAGAUGCAUGCCCACGUCGGUCUUCACCCGACUGGCCACCCACGCCCACUCCACCAUGAGCAGAGCGGGUCGCACCUCCUCACUGUCGCCUCCACUCACCCAGGCCUAGGAUGGGCACAUUGAUGAAGCAUGCUCAGAGAUGGGAUCUCACCACCCCUCCUUGCUGCGGCCCCCGAUGCCAGCCUCUGGCUCCUCCAGAUGGAGUUGCCACCUCAUCUCUGUCCCCAGCGCCCUCACCUCGGGAGGCCUCAGGCCACCAGCUUCAGUGCUUUCCCGGUGGCGUCUCUGGCGCGGGUUUACCCCUGAACCUGUAGAAACUCGGCCUCUUAGGAAAGGGUGGGGAGAACUGUAUCUCACGUUGCAGAAAAAUUCACAAGUGCACAUCAGGAAGCUGGGAAACAGUGUCUGCAGAAGACAGCAGUAAAUACAGAAGAUCUAGAACGCUCCAGGCCGCGUGAAUGGCUUCUUUGUUCAGCUUAGUGUUAGAGGUACACACCAGGUGGAGGAGACUCAGGUGGGCCCAUCACCAGCCCUGGCAACCCCAGACUCACUUCAGGCCUCUUUAAGGUCGCUUUGCAGAUGAUACCGUGAGUAAAUGCUUGUCUUAGAGAUUUUCAUAAACACAGACACAUAAGAAACUACGAAUCGACAACCUCCAGAGUGGGGGCCACAGCUGCCUGUCGGUGCAUUUCCGUCCUGUCAGGGUCUUUUGCUUUGGAUUUUAUGCUCACCAAAGCCGCGCGUGCACAUCAGGAGUCAAGAAGCACCAUGGGCGUGUGUGUUAGUUGUUCUUACACUGCUAUGAAGAAAUAUCUGAGAUGGGGUAAUUUAUAAAGGAAAGAGGCUUAAUUAACUCACAGUUCCACAGGGCUGGGGAGGCCUCAGGAAACUUAGAAUCAUGGCGGAAGGGGAAGCAAGGCACCUUCUUCACAAGGCGGCAGGAAGGAGAAGCGCAAGCAGGGGAGAUGCCAGGUGCUUGUAAAACCAACAGAUCUCAUGCAGACUCACUCACCAUCACAAGAACUGCAUGGGGGAGACAGCUCCCAUCCAUCUAAUUUCUUCCCACUGGGUUCCUCCCACGACACGUGGGGCUUAUGGGAACUACAAUUGAAGAUGAGAUUUGGGUGGGGACACAGACAGACCCUAUCAGGGCAUGAGUAACCUCAGGAGUAAUGCCUCCCACCUCCCAGAGGCGCUGUCUUGCCCUUCUCAAGGCCAAACCAAGUGGCCACUUUGGAAUGGGUUUAGGGCUGCUGACCUUACCUGGUGACCAGGGAGAACAGGUCACCCGAUAAGGUCUGCCCUCCCCGCUGCACACCUGCGCUCCCCACUCAUACCCGUCAGAGUGGCUUUCUCGGGGGUUGGAUCUGCCUCUGCUGUUGACGUGGUGAUGAUAAACACCUUGCUCACUGCUGAACCACGCAGGACCGUGUGACUGCUUUUCCUGCCUGGCUUUUGUUUUCCCUGGAGUUGUUGAUUGUUUUUCUUUUCAAUCACUUGUCACUAGUGUAUCUCCUCCUUUGCUCAGGUAUUCUUCCGGGUUUCAGUCUCGGGGCUGCUCUCCGUGGGUCUCCCACCAUUGGCCGAAUUCCUUUGGCUUCUCUUGGGUUGGGUCUUGGGUCUUCUCCUGGGAUUUGCUCCCUUGGUUUGGGGAGGGAGGCGCAUCAUUUUAUGGCCUCCUGAGAACAGGUGUUUGGGAUGUGUCCCUUUAAACAGAAUUCCCACGCUCCCUUCACUCGACUGCUGGCAUGUUAACGCCACCUCACUUGCUGUCCCCUCCCCUCUUCUGUCCUGUGGACACGUGUUAUUCUUGCCCUGACAAUUUGAGAAUGAGUUGUAGACUUGGUGCCCCUUUACUCCCAAAUGCUUGAACGUGACUUUGCUGCCAACGAGGACAUGACGCCGUACAAAGAUUGAAACGGGGGAGCUGACAUGGCAGCAGCACAGCCGUCUGCUCCAACUCACUGUGACUUCCCAGUUGUCCCGUUUUUGAAGAAUGCCGGCCAGUCAUCGAGUGCCCUUGGUUUGGGUACAAGGUGCGUUUUCCUAACUUGCGGGUCUGAAAGUGCGUCCAUUCCCCCUUCACGCCUGGUUGCGGUUUCGGCGGACUAGAAUUUCUACGCAGAAGUCUCCCUCAGGAUCAGACCGUAGCCCUUCCGGAAACCUCCAUGAUGCUGGACGAGAACCACCACCUGAUCCAGUGCAUCCUGGAGUACCAGAGCAAGGGCAAGACGGCCGAGUGCACGCAGUACCAGCAGAUCCUGCACCGGAACCUGGUAUACCUGGCCACGAUCGCAGACUCCAACCAGAACAUGCAGUCCCUGCUUCCUGCCCCGCCCACGCAGAACAUGAACCUGGGCCCUGGAGCCCUGACUCAGAGCGGCUCCAGCCAGGGCCUGCACUCUCAGGGCAGCCUGAGUGACGCCAUCAGCACGGGCCUGCCACCCUCCUCCCUCCUGCAGGGCCAGAUUGGCAACGGGCCGAGCCACGUGUCCAUGCAGCAGACGGCGCCUAACACGCUGCCCACCACCUCCAUGAGCAUCUCUGGGCCCGGCUACAGCCACGCGGGACCCGCCUCGCAGGGCGUCCCCAUGCAGGGGCAAGGCACCAUCGGCAACUACGUGUCUCGGACCAACAUCAACAUGCAGUCCAACCCAGUCUCCAUGAUGCAGCAGCAGGCGGCCACGUCGCACUACAGCUCGGCGCAGGGCGGCAGCCAGCACUACCAGGGCCAGUCGUCCAUCGCCAUGAUGGGGCAGGGCAGCCAGGGGAGCAGCAUGAUGGGGCAGCGGCCCAUGGCGCCCUACCGGCCCUCCCAGCAAGGCUCUUCCCAGCAGUACCUGGGCCAGGAGGAGUACUAUGGCGAGCAGUACAGCCACAGCCAGGGCGCCGCGGAGCCCAUGGGCCAGCAGUACUACCCCGACGGCCAUGGCGAUUACGCCUACCAGCAGUCAUCCUACACGGAGCAGAGCUACGACCGGUCCUUCGAGGAGUCCACGCAGCACUACUAUGAGGGGGGAAACUCCCAGUACAGCCAGCAGCAGGCCGGGUACCAGCAGGGUGCCGCGCAGCAGCAGACGUACUCCCAGCAGCAGUACCCCAGCCAGCAGAGCUACCCCGGGCAGCAGCAGGGCUACGGGUCUGCCCAGGGAGCCCCGUCACAGUACCCCGGCUACCAGCAAGGCCAAGGCCAGCAGUACGGAAGCUACCGAGCACCGCAGACAGCGCCGUCUGCCCAGCAGCAGCGGCCCUACGGCUAUGAACAGGGCCAGUAUGGAAAUUACCAGCAGUAAGGGACACACAUUCUGGCUGGAGCCCUUGUGGUAGCGUGUUCAUCCAGGGGCCGGAUGGGCUGGCGGCAGCUCUGGUGAAUUGUGACAUGUUGGUUACCUGUUCGCCCAGUGCCACGUCUGCAUGUGAAGCGUGCUCAUUUCAUGCUGGGUAUGACGCCGAGCGCACACCACUGGCGUGAGACAGCGCUUGGUGGUGUGAUACUUUUGGUGCUGUGUAUAGUAUUGUAUGUCGGUACACGGAGAGGUAUCCUUUUUUUGUCCCCCGCCCCCUUCUCAAUGUUUCUAGCUAGCUUUGGGGGUCAUUUUGUCAUCAGAGCAUUCUGUGCCCAGGGACAGGACAGAUCUCGAGGACACCACAGUCCACCUGUUCCCGUCAACAGACGUUAGGUCUCAUUUUCCUCCUCAUGCAGUGUUGUAGUGUGGGUUGUCAACUUUUCUUUAACUGGCUACGCCACAGCUGGACACACAUGCAGCCCCUGGAGGGCAGCCUCUUCCUGUGCCUCGAUGGGGUGGGUGGGAGGGCAUCUUCUGUGCGUUGGGUCAGUUUCUGUUACGUAACGAAAAGGAUAAACAUCUCCCACGGGAGAGGCCACAGAUGGCCACUUCCAGAGCUUGCCCAUUGCCUGUCUCUCGCCAAUUCCGUUUAUCCAAAAAGGUACAUGUUUUUGUAUUAAAAAGUAAACAGGGAUCAGUGACUGUAUUCCAAAUAAAUAUGAAUCCCUAAGGGCCGUGGACAAAUUGCCUAACCCAGGGCCAGCGGUAUUGCUGAAGGAAAGGGGCAGCUCUCUGGGAAGUGGGCCCUCAGAGAUUACUCUGGCUUUGACCCUUGUUUAGCUGAUGGUCAUUUCUGGGAUUGGAAUAUUUAAUAAGCCCAAUUCUAAGUUGAUAGGUAAUUUUAAAUAUUCAAACCAAAUCUUCCCAACAGUUGGCAAGUUGUUUAUUUUAUAUUAUUUCUUCCAGGACCUACUUGCUCAGAUCUCCAAGCAAGCAUUUCUUUUCUUUUAGGGAUGUCUGAAAGUCACAUCCAGUUACAUUACUGUGUUCUUUCUAAUGAAAAGUAAAGGUUUUAUAUAGAGAAACUUGAGUAAUUUUUACAUUUCUAAGACAUUAAAUCCCAUUUAAAUUCUGUGUGAACAUUAAAGACAGCACACUUGCAAAAGUAUGGUCAAAGGAAAAAAAUCCCACAUUUCAAUUAACAAGUAGCAUGGACAUUUGAUCAACCUUUAGUUGGAAUAAUAAUAUUCAUAUUUGCUAUGAAUCCUUUUAAAAAAAUCUUUGGAUAAAUGCUGACAGAUUUCCAAGAACUACCAAGAAAAUACAAGAGAUAUCCAAUGCUUGAUAUAUGAGGCCUAGUAAUAACGAUAUUUCUCUUUAAUUGAUGUUUUGUUUUAAAAGUUAAAAGUAAUUCUUGGCGUGGUGGUUCACGCCUGUAAUCCCAGCACUUUGGGAGGCCGAAGCGGGCGGAUCACCUGAGGUCGGGAGUUCGAGACCAGCCUGACCAACAUGGAGAAACCCCGUCCCUACUAAAAAUACAAAAUUAGCCAGGUAUGGUGGUGCAUACCUGUAAUCCCAGCUACUCGGGAACCUGAGGCAGGAGAAUGGCUUGAACCCAGGAGACAGAGGUUGUGGUGGGGCAAGAUCGCACCAUUGCACCCGAGCCUAGGCAACAAGAGUGAAAUUCCGUCUCAAAAAAAUAAAUAAAUAAAUAAAUAAAUAAGUUAAAAUUAAUUCUUUAUCCAGAGUCGGGUGCUUUAGAAUUUAUAAGUCACUUAUGUGUUUUGCUUGAAUUAAUUCUGACAGCCCCUAUGAGGAAAUCUGGAGGCAGGUAACAGUUCCCAUUUUAGAGAUGAAGAACUGAGGCACAGAUUAAAGGACUUGCCUGUGUUGAAUACCAGUCCUGUUCUAGGACAUUCUCCCCUCUCCUAGGAGACGGAUGUCACGCACAAAUGGGGAGAGAAGUGUUUAUUUUGUAGGCACUAAGGGUUUCUAAAACCCUUAACACUGGUAAGGGCUCAAAAAUAAACGUAUGUGUUCAUAUUCGAUCACCGAAAUGAGAGUUCUUAAUUGCUAAUUGACAAACGCGUUAGCAAUUUCAGUUAGGGAGUCAUCUCCCUUGAUUGUGUUCUUUUCCUGUCAAUUUUCAUAGACCUAAUUUGCAAACUCAAUCGGGGACUAAAAUUUCCCACUGAAAAUGUUAAACAUUUUAGAUAACUGUGAAGAUAGUUUAUUUUUAUUCCUUGCCAAUCUGGGAAUAUGCCUUUUUUGUGUGUUUGUGUGUUUUUUUAAGUGCUGUAUUAAUAAUACUUUCUGAAAGAAAAGGACACUUACCCCAAAACUUCAAUCUGAAAUGUCUUACAUUAAGAAUAUCUUGAAUGUUGUGUAUAUAUUUUAAAAAGCACUUUGCAAAAUAGUUUGUACAUUUAUUUCCUAAUUUAUACAUGAUUUUUGGUGUUAAUAUAUUUAAUGAUUAAUAACAGAAUGUUUAUUUAAUGUGCUGUCCAUUUUUAUGUAAUAUUAUGGGGAAAGUGAUGCCAGCAGUUCCUUUUCAUUAUUCUAUCUUCUGUCAUAUGAAUGUUGAGCAAAGCUUAGGCCAACAUGAAUUGUUUGUGAAGUGUGGUUGAUGGUGCUUUGUUUUUUUCUGACUACUUCUAUGGAAGGCCAGUGAAGAAGCAAAGGAAGACAUGAAAAUUGACGCUCAUUCUUCUUCCUAUUGUUCCCUGACAUCCAGCAAAUUGUGAAUUUGAAAAAUGAUGGCCAGUUUUCAGAAGUGCUGACAAAUUCAUAUUGGUAUGCAAAAGCUCAUCACCCAUUAAGGUUUGUUGUUGAAUCAACAGUACUCAGCAUAUUAAAACAGUACAUCAGAACUCAUGCCAACAGUCUUUAUGAUGGGAUUAAGGUGGACAAGAUCUCCUAAGAUCUGUGAAUGGGAUUAAGGUGGACAAGAUCUCCUAAGAUCUGAAAAGAAACCUUAAUACGCUCAUAUGGUUGGAGUGUUAAGUGAACCUCUGAUUUUGUCAGGGUUUUUCUACGUGUAGGCGUGAAUAGGGGGCACCCCUUCAAAACUGUACAAAGAAGACGACUGUUUUCCAUUUCCAUUUAAACAUUUUUAGCCACUUCAUUUCUAUUUAUUGAACAGGUCAAAUUUGUCUUGUUAUUUGUGAGUACAGUACAUUUAAAAAACAUCCUUAUCGGUUAUUUUUUUUUCAGUCGGAGUUUGACGUAUAAAUUGUUUAUGCUUUUGGUGUAAUCUCUUAAUAAACUGGUUCUUCAAAAAUCAUCCUAUAAAGUGAGUUUUCAUGAAGUUAA